CUCUCCUCCUUCUUCUCCGCUGCCGCCGCCGCUGCCCCUUUCCCGGCCGGUGGCUGCCGCUGCCGGUGCCGCCGCCGCCGCCUCCUGGGGGCCGCGAGCCGAGCGGAGACCGCCGCGGAGCGCGAGCGCCGCCCGCCCCGCCGCCCCGCCGGCCGCUCCAGGGCCGGGCCGGCUCGGCCGGCGCCCCCCGCGCCCCCAGCCCGCCCGCCCCCGCGGGCCCGGCCUGGCGCGGCCGCCCGCCGCCGCGCUCCUCCUCCUCCUCCUCCAGCGCCCGGCGGCCCGCUGCCUCCUCCGCCCGACGCCCCGCGUCCCCCGCCGCGCCGCCGCCGCCACCCUCUGCGCCCCGCGCCGCCCCCCGGUCCCGCCCGCCAUGCCCGGCCCGGCCGCGGGCAGCAGGGCCCGGGUCUACGCCGAGGUGAACAGUCUGAGGAGCCGCGAGUACUGGGACUACGAGGCUCACGUCCCGAGCUGGGGUAAUCAAGAUGAUUACCAACUGGUUCGAAAACUUGGUCGGGGAAAAUAUAGUGAAGUAUUUGAGGCCAUUAAUAUCACCAACAAUGAGAGAGUGGUUGUAAAAAUCCUGAAGCCAGUGAAGAAAAAGAAGAUAAAACGAGAGGUUAAGAUUCUGGAGAACCUUCGUGGUGGAACAAAUAUCAUUAAGCUGAUUGACACUGUAAAGGACCCCGUGUCAAAGACACCAGCUUUGGUAUUUGAAUAUAUCAAUAAUACAGAUUUUAAGCAACUCUACCAGAUCCUGACAGACUUUGAUAUCCGGUUUUAUAUGUAUGAACUACUUAAAGCUCUGGAUUACUGCCACAGCAAGGGAAUCAUGCACAGGGAUGUGAAACCUCACAAUGUCAUGAUAGAUCACCAACAGAAAAAGCUGCGACUGAUAGAUUGGGGUCUGGCAGAAUUCUAUCAUCCUGCUCAGGAGUACAAUGUUCGUGUAGCCUCAAGGUACUUCAAGGGACCAGAGCUCCUCGUGGACUAUCAGAUGUAUGAUUAUAGCUUGGACAUGUGGAGUUUGGGCUGUAUGUUAGCAAGCAUGAUCUUUCGAAGGGAACCAUUCUUCCAUGGACAGGACAACUAUGACCAGCUUGUUCGCAUUGCCAAGGUUCUGGGUACAGAAGAACUGUAUGGGUAUCUGAAGAAGUAUCACAUAGACCUAGAUCCACACUUCAACGAUAUCCUGGGACAACAUUCACGGAAACGCUGGGAAAACUUUAUCCAUAGUGAGAACAGACACCUUGUCAGCCCUGAGGCCCUAGAUCUUCUGGACAAACUUCUGCGAUACGACCAUCAACAGAGACUGACUGCCAAAGAGGCCAUGGAGCACCCAUACUUCUACCCUGUGGUGAAGGAGCAGUCCCAGCCUUGUGCAGACAAUGCUGUGCUUUCCAGUGGUCUCACGGCAGCACGAUGAAGACUGGAAAGCGACGGGUAAUGCGGCAUUGAUGCUUGCCAAUAAAACCAACCAACCAAACACAAACCUUGAAGGAAAACUACAGUGUGAUAAAAAGAAAUUCUUAUCAUUCCUUCUAAAUGCACAGAAGAGUAAAGACCUAAAAGUCUGUCAAAAAGCAAGAAAGAAACUCCCCAGUGCUAGUCUCCAGGGAGCUGUCACUGUGGCAGCAUGGGGAUGCACCUAGUUCAGGAUCUGAAGGAGCUCUGCCUUUGGAAUGCAUGGGAGAUAGAGACUCGGAGUUGUUGUACAUUUACCUUUGUUUAACAGGGCACCACUGUUGAAUUAACCCAUUCAGUCAACAAGCUCUGAAUGUCUGACUUCCUAUCUAUUCCAUUGUGGUCUGGGUUUCCUUUGGUGAAAUUCAGGCUCAAGUCUUAGCGAAAUGUCAGCAGUCUAUACUGACACACCAGCCUCAUUUACAAAAAGGAGAUAUUAAAACAGUGACAGUAUUUUUUUUUUAAGCUCUUUACAAAUCCACGUUUUAUGUAUUUUUUAAUGACAUGAGCUCUCCAGGAAAUGUACCUCAUCCCCGCAGUUUUCCUCCAAGUGGAUUCAUUUGGGAGCAAACUGCAGUCACUUUCACAAGAGUCCUCUUUGAUGUCAGGAGGGAUCACGAAACCUUGCAAUGCCAUGAACUGGUCCAUGGUUAUCAUCAAAAGUUCCAUGCUAAGUGCAUAACUUGGAGCUCACUAUAACCUUUGUUGAUUUCCCUAACCAUAAAAUCUUGUUGCUAUUUUUUUGUUGCUUUUUCUUUUUUUUUUUUUUUUUUUUUUUUGGCAGCCUUGUAAGGAGAACUUCACCAUUUCCCAGCACAUCCCUAUGUGUGCGCCUAUUUUAAUGCACCUCUCUGAAACAGAGACCUUUUUGUUCACAACCAUAACUAAAGCUGGAAAGUCAGUCUUCAGGCAAGGCGAGGGAGGAAAACAUCCCAUUAGAAUUUUUUCAGGAAAGACUUAUGGAAAAAAAUAUCUCUCUCCCACCUCCUUUUAUCCCCAUGAGACACAGUUUCCCACUGUAAUCAGGGUAAUAUGCAUUUGUAAGUUCUGAUAUGUGAUACAUUUAUGUGAUGGCAAAGAUAAGUCUGUCUUGCAUGCAGGUACUAGAGUUGUGUGGGCAGGGUCAUCUGAAACUCAAGCAACUCAGAGGAAUAUACAAGGGGCUUGGGGAAGAAAAUGGUGCUCCCGGAGCAAGUGUUGGAUCCAUUUUGCAAACCUUCAUGUUAGCAGAGAAAGCUAGAGUUUGUUUAAACAAAAAUAGGGCUGAUUUCAUUUUGGGGACUCAGGAGCAACAUGGUUUGUAGGCAGUCCCCUCACCCCAGCUGCAGGGCCAUGCCACAGCUGUGGGGACUUCACACACCUAGGCUAGAACUAGAGGUGUCUACCACAUCACCCUUUAAGAUUUCUUUAUUAACUAUUUAAUAAUGCCAUACAUUUUUAUAAGGUUAGAUGUUUGUUUGAAACAUUUGUUUACAUUCCAUAUUCCAAUAAAAUCUUAUUGGUAUUGGUAGCAGAUCCUACUCUAAAUGUAGAUUCUAUUUUUGUCGUUUGGUCUGUGGGAACUUAAAAUACAAAUGAAACUCUUCUCUUAUUAUAGAGUUGAGUUUAUAGAGUAAAAAAUAAAUAAGAUCCCAAAGCCAAGGAAUGCAUUCAGUUAAGGUUCUCAUACCAAUGCUGCCUGCUUGCAUUGCACAUUCUGUAUACUAAUGUAAACAUUUGUUCUACCUGAAAAUCAAAAGCAAGAUGUGAGCUCUUUGGCUAAACCUGUAUUGAUAUGUCAGGCAGCAAAACUCAGUGUUUGAGAUUAUCAAAAGCCUUCUAAUAUGCCCUUAUAGGCAAUCCUGAAGCAUUGGUUAUCAUCAGGGAGAUGUGCCACUGCGUGUCUUUCCUGCUCCCCCUCCAAUCUCCUUUAUCACCCCACCCCACUCCUCAGCCCUCCCUUUUUUUUUUUAAGUUGCCUGUCUGGACCAGGCAAGAGGUGCCUACUGGAGGGUCUUGGUGAAGCGGUAACUCCAUUCCUUUCCCUUGGGUCCCCCAAAGGUAAUAAAAGUACCUGGAGGAGAAUAGUCAGGUGAUUGACCUCUGCCUGUCUCUCUGACGGUGAUGUAGGUGCAGACACCGCCUGCCUGCCUUGUCCUGGGGUUUUGUAACUGCAGCUUUGACACAGGCAUUCUUCCUUUGAAGCACACAGCUUGCUUUUCCAGCACCUAGACUUUUACCUCUCUUCAUGCCUUAGACUUAGACCAUAACUGGGCUUGAAAUGCUCACCCCUUCCUGGGUCUGGUCUUGGCACCUAGGCUAUUCCUUUCCAAACUGAAGUGAGUCCAGUUUCAGACCAUCUCUUUUCCUGUCUCCAAAAACCAUUUUUGUUUCCAAACCUAGCUCCCCCGAAAUUUUAAGACUAUUUACCUAGAUUCGGAGAUGGUCUUGGAGAGUUCCAAAAGGGGUGUGUGUGUGUCUGUGUGUGUGUCUGUGUGUGUGUCUGUGUGUGUGUCUGUGUGUGUGUCUGUGUGUCUAAUAUUUAGACUAAACCAUGGUAAAUGUACGCACCCAGUAUCCUUUUCAGUUAGCAUAUUCUUUCUUAAACUCAUCUCAGUACUUUUCAUUUGUUUGCUUCAUUAUCUUAAACAGGUUAAAAGUGCCUAUGAUAAGGACUUAAUUAUUUCCUAAAGAAAAGCAAAAAAUGUGGGGAACAGGGUAGUGUUAUACUAUCAUCUCAGGUACUGCCUAUGUUCAAGAACAUAGACCUGGUAUGGUGAGAACAAAAGGUUCCUAUGCCAAAUCCAGAUGGCUAUAUCAUUUGUUGGCUACAAGUGAGCCUGACUGCAAGGUUUGCUUCUGCUGAGAAAUCCCAUGGUGAGAGUAGAACUCAUGAAGUGCUGAGUCACAUUUGCACCUCUGGUGUGGUGGCAGUUCACUCUCCCCUGGAUGCUGUCAGCUGGCCUUGCUUUCAUCCUAUCCCUGUAGGCAGGGUAGGUGGCUGGGUAGGAGAAGCUAUUGAGUGUAUGACGCAGACCAAGCUUUCCUGGGCCUUCUCACCAACUAGAGAAGCGCUGAUGUCGUUCAUUGAGGCACUUAAACACCAGUCACUCAGCCAGGCCUCCUCCCAGACAUUCUGUAACAUGUCAGCACUCACAAGGUUUAAAGCAAAUGUGUUCCCUUGCAGAGAGGAAGGUGCUCUCAGACUGAUAGAUUAGAGGAGACAGACAAACUCGUAAUCCUUGGGGACUUGAAGAGAGUGGCUAGGGGAAGGGCUGUUAAAAGAAAAGGGACCAAUAAGAAAAUCCAUCUAAAGGUAGCUCUUGAGGAGGAAAUUAACUUCUUGAGGGGAUAAAUUAGAGGGUACCAAGUUUAUGUUCUGGAAUGUACCCUGGGGAGGGCGCUGCCCACUGGAUUGGUCCCAGUGGACUGAAAGGUGGUGCUCUCGAGUCAGGCGCUUAGUCCCAGAGAGAGCUGGGUGCCGCGGGGCUCGUGGUCUGUGCCUACUCAGGGAAAUGACUUAGGUUCUCCCAGGUGCUCUGUUGAUAAGGAUGGAAGCAGAACUACUUUGAGACACAAGCAACAAUUGGAAGAGUUUUUUUAUAUGAACUGAAAUAGAUCUAAGAGAGCCUGGUUAACAGUUUCCUUUAAUACCAGUUCAGAUUAAAUGGUUACUUUAGGAACCUGUGUUACUGUGUGAGCACCCACAGAAACAAGCAAACUUAUUUCCUACAAAAAAUGAGGGGAUAAUAACCGAUCAGAGUCACAGUCGUUUCAAUAUAAACCCUUCCGAAAGCAAAAGCAGGGACCACAUGAGCACACAAGAAGCCAAAGUUUGUCAGUGAUCUUAAUAAAUUAAGACUGAGUAACAUCCUGCCUUUAGAAAAAAAUAACCCCGAGGUGGAGACCAGGGCAGGGGAGGUGGCGGAGAAGCAUCGGGCCAGAUCAACCGUUAAUAACAUGCUUCUGAGCUAUGUGGAUGUAUAAAUGAAAACACCCCCAACUAGGUAUUGUAGAGGCUGGAAAAAGAUGUGAUGGGAUUAUACAGGUGAUGCAUAUUUUUGUUUUGAGACUCAACAAUGUGCUACAAAUGUGAUACUUAACCCUGAACUGCAUGUAUUGGGGAUUGUUUUUUAAAAAGAAAAAAAACAACUUUGAAUCAAUAAAUUAACAGUUUUUCACUUGCUGGCUCUUCUUGCUGUAAAUGGUGACUAAGAGGUUGGGACAGAAAUCUUGACAACUAGUGGAAAACUUGGAUAAUCUUCAAGGACCAUGGAGCCUUCUGUUUCCUUCUGUUUGCAGAAAAGCAACACUGCCUGGGUUGUGAUCCUUUACAAGUGACUACUUCAGACACAAUUGGCCACCUCUUUGUAUCACUGGAUGACUGAUGUAUGAUUUAUGUGCUGCUGCCCUUAGAGGGAAGAAAAAUGCCAUGUUAAAUCCUGUUUUCUUAAAUAAAAAUGUUGACAAUAACCAGCCUUCCCAAGUGGGAGACAAACCAUUGCUAUGAGGACCUUAACUUGUAUUUCCUGUCUCUUUGGGGGAGAGGGGAGGGAUAAACCUUGAAUUGCAAAGAUGUGUGUUACACCUUGAUGUGAAAACUUUCCUUUGGCAGAAGUGGGGCUAGAGUGGUGUCCUGUUGGGAGUGUUCCGUUUUUAUGUACUUGCUUCUGAGUCGCGCCACUCAGACACCUGCCUCUUGGGAUUGACUGUUUUAGUGCAUGACUUUAACCUUGUGGCCUGGUGCUCUGCAUUUGUGAAACACUCUCCCUAGCCCCAUUCCUUGCAGCACAUGCUAUUAUUUGGCAGGUGGUGGUAUCUUUAAUUAAUGUGCUUUCUUUAAUUAGUGUGCUUUCUUCUCACUGAGCCUCUGAAGUUGGGUGCUUGGAAUCAGCUGAAGUGUUUAAAGGCAAAUAUAGUCAUUUCUUUCUUAACCUCAUGCACCAUGCAGCCCUUCUCAAAUCAAAUACUACGCAGUGGAACCCUUCCUUUACCCAAAGAAAGUUUUCAUGAAAUGAUUUUGUGUGUGUGACAGCUUCCCAGGUGCAUAGUCCUUCCUCAGUACUGUAGUGCUGUUCUGGGAGGCACUGCUUCUAGAAUUCCACUGCCGGCAUCUCACCACCCACUUGCUAUGCUGGACCUGGAAGGAGAAAUGAGGUUUUCAGGCCAUGCCAGGCAGCUAGCUGUUUCCAGGGGAGAGUUAAAAAUAUUUGAGCUCACUUACUGCUCUUUGUUUAUUAGUGGACUCAGCCCUUUUUCUGAGUAAAUACAGACCCCGUCUUAGUCCUAAGACACCUCAGAUAAUCAGGUCAGGUCUGAGGGGGACCUAGAGCUGACUGCUGAAUUUGUAGCUUGACUGGCACAGAAUGGUCAAGAGGCUCUGAGGCUUCUCCAUCAGCACCCUGGACCCGAGGGAUGGGGUAGAGUGGAAGACCUGGUCACAACACACGUGGUGCCCAGAGCACCCGUCCUGUGACAGAAGGCCGUGCUAGAGACCAUCUCUGUCAUGAUAAUCAGAAGAGGAAGGCAGAGGGUACUGUUGGAAACCUGAACUCAGCGAGUUCUCACAGGGUUCUCCACCAAGUGGCAUGGGAGGGCCGAGCUUGCAUUCUAGCACAGGCCCUCCUACACGUGGAGGCCUCCCCUCGCCCGCUCAGGUUGAUUAAUGACGUCUUUCCCUCCUCCCGUCUCUUUCCCCAGGUCUGUUGCGGUUCUCCCACUUUUCCAUAAGCAGAACAAGAACCAAAUCAAACGUCUUAACGCGUAUAGAGAGAUCACGUUCCGUGAGCAGACACAAAACGGUGGCAGGUUUGGCGAGCACGAACUAGACCAAGCGAAGGGCAGCCCACCACCGUAUAUCAAACCUCACUUCCGAAUGUAAAAGGCUCACUUGCCUUUGGCUUCCUGUUGACUUCUUCCCGACCCAGAAAGCAUGGGGAAUGUGAAGGGUAUGCAGAAUGUUGUUGGUUACUGUUGCUCCCCGAGCCCCUCGACUCGUCCCGUGGCCGCCUGUUUUUCCAGCAAACCACGCUAACUAGCUGACCACAGACUCCACAGUGGGGGGACGGGCGCAGUAUGUGGCAUGGCGGCAGUUACAUAUUAUUAUUUUAAAAGUAUAUAUUAUUGAAUAAAAGGUUUUAAAAGAAA